AGUGGAGACUCUUAACACCAGUUCUCUGGCAUCUGUGAGUUUGAGUGUGGGCCAUCAUCUUCUUCCUUCUGCUCUCUCCCUCUCCACAUUUCCCGGUACCAUCUGAUCCAUCAGGCCCUUCUUUGCUCAGGCCUGAAGGACUCAGGCCUGUGAGAGAGGACGGCCCCGUUGUCGGCCAAGACACCUUUGGGCGAGGAGCAGCGAACAGGGCCUGUCCAUCUCAGACGUCAGCCCCCUGAAGGCCUGAGCAAUGGGCAACGUGAUGGAGGGAAAGUCAGUGGAGGAGCUGAGCAGCACCGAGUGCCACCAGUGGUACAAGAAGUUCAUGACUGAGUGCCCCUCUGGCCAACUCACCCUCUAUGAGUUCCGCCAGUUCUUCGGCCUCAAGAACCUGAGCCCGUCGGCCAGCCAGUACGUGGAACAGAUGUUUGAGACUUUUGACUUCAACAAGGACGGCUACAUUGAUUUCAUGGAGUACGUGGCAGCGCUCAGCUUGGUCCUCAAGGGGAAGGUGGAACAGAAGCUCCGCUGGUACUUCAAGCUCUAUGAUGUAGAUGGCAACGGCUGCAUUGACCGCGAUGAGCUGCUCACCAUCAUCCAGGCCAUUCGCGCCAUUAACCCCUGCAGCGAUACCACCAUGACUGCAGAGGAGUUCACCGAUACAGUGUUCUCCAAGAUUGACGUCAACGGGGAUGGGGAACUCUCCCUGGAAGAGUUUAUAGAGGGCGUCCAGAAGGACCAGAUGCUCCUGGACACACUGACACGAAGCCUGGACCUUACCCGCAUCGUGCGCAGGCUCCAGAAUGGCGAGCAAGACGAGGAGGGGGCUGACGAGGCCGCUGAGGCAGCCGGCUGAGUGCACCGCCCGGCUGCUUCUGCACUAGCGGGUGGGGUGGUAUGGUGGUGCCUGUUGGUGGUGUUCUUGUCUUAACCCUAGAUAGAAUCUAAUGAACUCAGAGGCUUAGCUCGCCUCUUUAGGGUCCAUGGUGGCAGCAGAGAGGCAGAAGUGGGAGUCCAGAGCCAGGAACAGUGAAGGAUGGUUCCUGGCCCCUCUGAGUGACAGCUGGUGGCAGCACUCCUUGCUGGGGGGCACUGUUCAACAUCCCUCUGCCGUCGGGUGACCCCCUAGCCCUUCUGACUCCUCUCCCAGCUUUUCCCAGCUUUCCCCACUGAGCUUCUCCAGUCCAUGCUCUUCUGGACGUGGACUCUCUGAGGCAGAACUGAGCUUUUCCAGGCCUCUUAUGGAAUCCUGCAGAUCCAGUGGCUGCAGCUUCAAUCCCAGUGCUGCAAUCACACAUCCAUUCUGCCCUGGGGGACCCUGGAGCCUACUUGUGCGCUUUGCAUUUCAUUGAUUGACGCCUCCCUUCAACAAGCAUUUACUGAGCGCCUACUAUGUACUAAUGCUAGAUGUUAGAUGUACAAAGAAGACAGUUUUCAUCCUCUAGGAACUCAUAGGCUAAUGGUGAGACACACAGACAAACAUCAUUAUAAUAAAAUAUGCUAAGAGAA